GUCGGCCAUUUUAGGUGGUCCGCGGCGGCGCCAUUAAAGCGAGGAGGAGGCGAGAGCGGCCGCCGCUGGUGCUUAUUCUUUUUUAGUGCAGCGGGAGAGAGCGGGAGUGUGCGCCGCGCGAGAGUGGGAGGCGAAGGGGGCAGGCCAGGGAGAGGCGCAGGAGCCUUUGCAGCCACGCGCGCGCCUUCCCUGUCUUGUGUGCUUCGCGAGGUAGAGCGGGCGCGCGGCAGCGGCGGGGAUUACUUUGCUGCUAGUUUCGGUUCGCGGCAGCGGCGGGUGUAGUCUCGGCGGCAGCGGCGGAGACACUAGCACUAUGUCGGAGGAGCAGUUCGGCGGGGACGGGGCGGCGGCAGCGGCAACGGCGGCGGUAGGCGGCUCGGCGGGCGAGCAGGAGGGAGCCAUGGUGGCGGCGACACAGGGGGCAGCGGCGGCGGCGGGAAGCGGAGCCGGGACCGGGGGCGGAACCGCGUCUGGAGGCACCGAAGGGGGCAGCGCCGAGUCGGAGGGGGCGAAGAUUGACGCCAGUAAGAACGAGGAGGAUGAAGGCCAUUCAAACUCCUCCCCACGACACUCUGAAGCAGCGACGGCACAGCGGGAAGAAUGGAAAAUGUUUAUAGGAGGCCUUAGCUGGGACACUACAAAGAAAGAUCUGAAGGACUACUUUUCCAAAUUUGGUGAAGUUGUAGACUGCACUCUGAAGUUAGAUCCUAUCACAGGGCGAUCAAGGGGUUUUGGCUUUGUGCUAUUUAAAGAAUCGGAGAGUGUAGAUAAGGUCAUGGAUCAAAAAGAACAUAAAUUGAAUGGGAAGGUGAUUGAUCCUAAAAGGGCCAAAGCCAUGAAAACAAAAGAGCCGGUUAAAAAAAUUUUUGUUGGUGGCCUUUCUCCAGAUACACCUGAAGAGAAAAUAAGGGAGUACUUUGGUGGUUUUGGUGAGGUGGAAUCCAUAGAGCUCCCCAUGGACAACAAGACCAAUAAGAGGCGUGGGUUCUGCUUUAUUACCUUUAAGGAAGAAGAACCAGUGAAGAAGAUAAUGGAAAAGAAAUACCACAAUGUUGGUCUUAGUAAAUGUGAAAUAAAAGUAGCCAUGUCGAAGGAACAAUAUCAGCAACAGCAACAGUGGGGAUCUAGAGGAGGAUUUGCAGGAAGAGCUCGUGGAAGAGGUGGUGGCCCCAGUCAAAACUGGAACCAGGGAUAUAGUAACUAUUGGAAUCAAGGCUAUGGCAACUAUGGAUAUAACAGCCAAGGUUACGGUGGUUAUGGAGGAUAUGACUACACUGGUUACAACAACUACUAUGGAUAUGGUGAUUAUAGCAACCAGCAGAGUGGUUAUGGGAAGGUAUCCAGGCGAGGUGGUCAUCAAAAUAGCUACAAACCAUACUAAAUUAUUCCAUUUGCAACUUAUCCCCAACAGGUGGUGAAGCAGUAUUUUCCAAUUUGAAGAUUCAUUUGAAGGUGGCUCCUGCCACCUGCUAAUAGCAGUUCAAACUAAAUUUUUUGUAUCAAGUCCCUGAAUGGAAGUAUGACGUUGGGUCCCUCUGAAGUUUAAUUCUGAGUUCUCAUUAAAAGAAAUUUGCUUUCAUUGUUUUAUUUCUUAAUUGCUAUGCUUCAGAAUCAAUUUGUGUUUUAUGCCCUUUCCCCCAGUAUUGUAGAGCAAGUCUUGUGUUAAAAGCCCAGUGUGACAGUGUCAUGAUGUAGUAGUGUCUUACUGGUUUUUUAAUAAAUCCUUUUGUAUAAAAAUGUAUUGGCUCUUUUAUCAUCAGAAUAGGAAAAAUUGUCAUGGAUUCAAGUUAUUAAAAGCAUAAGUUUGGAAGACAGGCUUGCCGAAAUUGAGGACAUGAUUAAAAUUGCAGUGAAGUUUGAAAUGUUUUUAGCAAAAUCUAAUUUUUGCCAUAAUGUGUCCUCCCUGUCCAAAUUGGGAAUGACUUAAUGUCAAUUUGUUUGUUGGUUGUUUUAAUAAUACUUCCUUAUGUAGCCAUUAAGAUUUAUAUGAAUAUUUUCCCAAAUGCCCAGUUUUUGCUUAAUAUGUAUUGUGCUUUUUAGAACAAAUCUGGAUAAAUGUGCAAAAGUACCCCUUUGCACAGAUAGUUAAUGUUUUAUGCUUCCAUUAAAUAAAAAGGACUUAAAAUCUGUUAAUUAUAAUAGAAAUGCGGCUAGUUCAGAGAGAUUUUUAGAGCUGUGGUGGACUUCAUAGAUGAAUUCAAGUGUUGAGGGAGGAUUAAAGAAAUAUAUACCGUGUUUAUGUGUGUGUGCUUAUUUGUUUGAAUGAUUUUAUUUUCCAUUUCUCAAAGGUUUUAUUUUUUUGGUUAGGGCCUUAAAAUUUCAGGACUGUGAUUAUUAGUAUGUGUGCCUAAGGAACUUUUUGAGUCACUCUUAAGAAAGUGAAACUGAAGAGUCUAAGUGAUAACUAUAGGAUUAAGUCAGAAUUGUUUUUCCUGUCAUUUGUUGGAAGCUUCUUGAGUUCUGUUAUUAGCAUUCAGGGAAUUGAUACCCAUCAACUUGAAUGGAAAAUCGUUUGUAGGUAUUACUUAAGUGAAUGUUAAGAGUUCCACCCUGAGUGGUAAUCUAAGGCUGUGCAGUCAGUUACUUCAGACUGCUCAGAAUAGUUCAUUAGAAAGGUAACAAAUGAGAAAUGUAUUAUUAUACAGUUCUAUAGUAGUGAAGUGAUGGAAUACCUUUCUUACUUUUGUGGAGUUACAUCUGAUGCUAAGAAUUUGACCUCCAACUAAGCAAACAUUUUAAUGAGCAAAAGUUAGUGUUAUUAAAGUUUUUUUAUGAUAGAUCCAAAUUGAGGACCUGUGUCCUGUUUUUAUAAGAUUGCAACCCAGCUAUGCUCAUUUGUUUAUGUUUUGUAUAUGGCUGCUUUUGUGUUACAGUGGUAGAGUUUAGUAGUUAGGACAGAGACCUGCAAAGCAAAAUAAUUUACAGUCUGGCCCUUUACAGAAAAGUUUGCUGACUCAUGGUCAAAAUAAAUGAAAAUUUUUUGUGUUAGGGUUGUUAAGCUAGGGUUCUUUUUGGUAUCAUAUGCUUAUUUUAUGUAAAUCUCUCAAUAAAAAAUUAUUUUUAAGAGA